AGGUGUGGCCCCAGCUCCUCACACCUCCUGGCAACCGGGCCUCCUCAUGAGAAUUCCUAGAAAUAAGCACAUGAGCACUCGGAGCUCAGAACACGGUGCUGCCCAGGCACUGUUGCUGGGACAGAGGCCCUCCAGAGCACCAGGAUGGAAUCAUCCCCGGGUGAGGGCUCCCCUCAUUCAGGGGCCAGGGCUGGCAGGGACCGGGAAGAAGUCUACUCUGGAGACCGCAGGAAGCAGAGAGGAGACGAGGGUCCCUGUGCUGAGCUGGGGGCUGCCCUCAGUCCUCACCACCCUUCCCCGAAAUCCUACUGUCCCCACCAAUCAGGGGGCCACGGAACCCAAUAGAGACCAUUGGGCAGUGGGGCUUUCAACGUGCUGUACUCUCCCUUAAAGUGUUGCAAGGAAGUCGCCAAAUGAGACUAAUGACUCCCCCACAUCAGAUCCUUAUCCUGCUGGUCCCCCUCCUCCCUAUGGUCCUCCUCACCAGAUGUACUUUGAAGGCCCCCAAGUUGUUCAGCUGUAUGCCGGCAUGUCCGUGGUGGGGACGUCCAUGCCGGUGCAGGCCGUGUGUCCCUACUGUGGAAACCGCAUCAUCACGGUGACGACCUUUGUCCCGGGUGCCCUCACCUGGCUGCUGUGUACCACCCUCUUCCUGUUCGGGUACGUCCUGGGCUGCUGCUUCCUGGCAUUCUGCAUAAGGAGCCUAAUGGACGUGAAGCACUCGUGUCCCGUGUGUCAGCGCGAGCUCUUCUACUACCACCGCCUGUGAGCCCCCAAGAAAUAAAUGCCAGGGGUGCCACCUGGGCACACCCGUGUCUAUGUCC